GCAGAGACGCCAUGUACCGGCUCAUGUCAGCAGUGACUGCCCGGGCUGCCGCCCCCGGGGGCUUGGCCUCAAGCUGCGGACGACGCGGGGUCCAUCAGCGCGCCGGGCUGCCGCCUCUCGGCCACGGCUGGGUCGGGGGCCUCGGGCUGGGGCUGGGGCUGGCGCUCGGGGUGAAGCUGGCAGGUGGGCUGAGGGGCGCGGCCCCGGCGCAGUCCCCCGCGGCCCCCGACCCUGAGGCGUCGCCUCUGGCCGAGCCGCCACAGGAGCAGUCCCUCGCCCCGUGGUCUCCGCAGACCCCGGCGCCGCCCUGCUCCAGGUGCUUCGCCAGAGCCAUCGAGAGCAGCCGCGACCUGCUGCACAGGAUCAAGGAUGAGGUGGGCGCACCGGGCAUAGUGGUUGGAGUUUCUGUAGAUGGAAAAGAAGUCUGGUCAGAAGGUUUAGGUUAUGCUGAUGUUGAGAACCGUGUACCAUGUAAACCAGAGACAGUUAUGCGAAUUGCUAGCAUCAGCAAAAGUCUCACCAUGGUUGCUCUUGCCAAAUUGUGGGAAGCAGGGAAACUGGAUCUUGAUAUUCCAGUACAACAUUAUGUUCCCGAAUUCCCAGAAAAAGAAUAUGAAGGUGAAAAGGUUUCUGUCACAACAAGAUUACUGAUUUCCCAUUUAAGUGGAAUUCGUCAUUAUGAAAAGGACAUAAAAAAGGUGAAAGAAGAGAAAGCUUAUAAAGCCUUGAAGAUGAUGAAAGAGAAUGUUGCAUUUGAGCAAGAAAAAGAAGGCAAAAGUAAUGAAAAGAAUGAUUUUACUAAAUUUAAAACAGAGCAGGAGAAUGAAGCCAAAUGCCGGAAUUCAAAACCUGGCAAGAAAAAGAAUGAUUUUGAACAAGGCGAAUUAUAUUUGAGAGAAAAGUUUGAAAAUUCAAUUGAAUCCCUAAGAUUAUUUAAAAAUGAUCCUUUGUUCUUCAAACCUGGUAGUCAGUUUUUGUAUUCAACUUUUGGCUAUACCCUACUGGCAGCCAUAGUAGAGAGAGCUUCAGGAUGUAAAUAUUUGGACUAUAUGCAGAAAAUAUUCCAUGACUUGGAUAUGCUGACGACUGUGCAGGAAGAAAACGAGCCAGUGAUUUACAAUAGAGCAAGGUAAAUGAAUACCUUCUGCUGUGUCUAGCUAUAUCGCAUCUUAACACUAUUUUAUUAAUUAAAAGUCAAAUUUUCUUUGUUUCCAUUCCAAAAUCAACCUGCCACAUUUUGGGAGCUUUUCUACAUGUCUGUUUUCUCAUCUGUAAAGUGAAGGAAGUAAAACAUGUUUAUAAAGUACACUAAGACCCUUUGAUGAAAGAUAGCAAUAAUAUUAAUAAUUCAAACAUGAAUAACUAAACCAAAAUUGCACCCACCAUGAGCAUCUGUAAUUUGCUCUUUAACCAUUCCUUUUUUAGGUUUUAACUAAUACUUUGUUUACGUGUUAUUAGUUUUUAAUUGUUUUCAUACUGUUUUGAAAUAAUUUUAUACUUAUAGAAAAGUUGCAAGAGUAGUACAAAGGAUUCACAUAUCCUCUUUACUCAGAUUCCCUUAAUGUUAGUUUACCGCAUUUGCAUUACCUUUCUGUCUACAUAUGUGUUUGUUUCUGAACCAUUUGGAAAUAAGUUGUAGACGUGAUACCCCUUUACCUAUAAAUAUUUACAUGUGUAUUUUCUAAAAACAAGGACAUUCAGGGCCGGGUGCAGUGGCUCACGCCUGUAAUCCCAACACUUUGGAAGGCCGAGGUGGGUGGAUCACCUGAGGUCAGGAGUUCAAGACCAGCCUGGCCAAUGUGGUGAAAUCAACCCUCUCUCUACUAAAAAUGCAAAAAUUAGCCAGGUGUGGUGGCGGGUGCCUAUAAUCCCAGCCACGCGGGAGGCUGAGGCAGGAGAAUCGCUUGAACCCAGGAGGUGGAGUUGCAGUAAGCCAAGAUCGUGCCCCUGCACUUCAGGCUGGGCGAAAGAGUGAGACUCCAUGUCAAAAAAGGAAAAAAAAAAAAAAAAAAAGGACAUUUGGGAAAUUAACAUAGAUACAAUGCUUUUAUUAAAUCUACAGACCUUACUCAAAUUUUGCCAGUUGUUCCAAUAAUGUCCUUUAUAGCAAAAGAGCAGAAAAACUUUUUUUUCUGGUCUAGGAUCUAAUCCAUGAUCUCACAUUGCAUUUACUUGUCAUAUCUAUCAGAAGUCACUUGACAUCAGUUUGUCCCAUUAUUGCUGAUGGUAUUUUAAUCACUUUUUGAGGUGGUGCCUGUCAGGUUAUUGUAAAGUUACUAUUUUUACUUUAUAAUUAACAAGUAUAUUUGGAGGAGAUAAUUUGAGAUGAUGUAAAAAUCCUCUUUCUCAUCAAACUUUCUACUAGUUUUAGCAUCUAUCAGUGAUUCAUGACUGAAUCAGUUAUUACAGUGAUGGUUGUCAAAUGGUGAUUUUCUAAUUCCAUCAUCCAUUCUGUAUUUAUCAGUUGGCAUUCUAUUAUAAGAAGGUGCGGGCCGGGGCGGUGGCUCACGCCUGUAAUCCCAUCACUUUGGGAGGCUGAGGUGGGCGGAUCACAUGAGACCAAGUUUGAGACCAGCCUGGCCAACAUGGCGAAACCCCAUCUCUACUGAAAAUACAAAAAAUCAGCCGGGCAUGGUGGCAUACACUUGUAAUCUCGGCUGCUCGGGAGUCUGAGGCAGGAGAAUCUCUUGAACCCAGGAGGCAGAGGUUGCAGUGAGCCAAGAUCAUGCCACUGCACUCCAGCCUGGGCGACAAAGUGAGACUCCAUCUCAGAAAAAAAAGUGCUUUCCCUUCUCUCUUAUUUAUUUAUUCAUACCAGUAUGCACUCAUGGAUUCUUAUUUUAGUCAAUGAGUUAUAAUCUGUCACUGUCAUUAUUUAAUAUGUUGCUUUUAAAAUAGUAUAUGAAAUAAUAAAACUGUAACAGUAAAUGGUUAUUAGAUUGCUUA